CUUUUUUUUUUUUUUAAUCCACUUGAAAAAGUCUGUGAAGCAGGGUCGCGGUUUACAGUUAUAAAGUUCCUUACGGAAGCUAAACAUCCAGAUCCCUCUGCCCAUCCCCGUUUAGAGGGUACUCUUUUUGGAUCAGUUGUUCUUCGUUUAUUAAAACUCAAAAUGAUUAUCCUUCGAAAUCUGCUCAUUGAGUUCUGUGGAGUAAGGGGGAGUGGGUGAGGGAAGGGGCAGCCACUAAGGGCUUUGGCACGGUGUGGGGUGCUGGCCCUGCCUUUCCCACCAGCGGGCACCUUCCCUGGGUUAGAGCAGCUGGUUAUAUAAACAUUCAUCACGGGGUGAAGAAUAGGGAGGAUGUUGUGUGUUCCAAGUACUGCAGGGCCUGGUACCCUUGUCAUCUGACCCGGUGCUCACCACUGUCCUAAGCAUCCGUCUCUAUUACAUAGCAGGGAGUGGGGCUGAGGGAGGCGAAGGGACUGGUCCAGGGUCACCCAGCCUUGUGACAAGUGACCUGUGCUGGCUGCUGAGGGCGGUGUUGACUUGGACUGGAUUUUCCUUUCUGAAUCAAAGAACAGCAGAGUAGGCCGUGAACGAGGCCUGGGGUAGGUAGAAUUUACUAUUGGAAAAUGCCUUUGUGACAUCGCGUUCCAUGUAACGAGGCCAUUUCCAUGCUGCAGUUGUAGUUCUGUAGUAAUAACUCUUACCCACAUGAUCAUUUGAUGUUCAUGUGGCCAUGGUGCACUCUGAGAAGUUGCCUACAUGCUGUUACCAGUCCCCUUCCAUGUCAGUAUCAAUUGCUACAAGAAAGAUAUUUUAAUUUUACUAUUUAGGUCAAAAUGCUGGUAAGUGGCCACCUUGUAAAAAACAAAGGAAGUAGUUACCUUCAAAGUCUCAUAAUGUGUGUGUGGAAACUGCAAUUGAAACAUUUGCAACAUGGGACAGUUUUAAUGUGACAGGCUUUGUGGUGUCUUUUAGGAAAAUUGGGAGGGUUUUAUAAGGAAAAGUUCAGAAAGUUUUCUAAAGAUAUGGAAGGACCACAUCUCAUGUGAGGGGGGAGAGGUUAGUAAAGCCAUGGGGAUGAAGGACAAGGAGUGGAUUGGUUAUUAGGAACAAGCCAGAAAUCCAAGAUCCCAUGUAGAAAAUUUAAAUACUCCUCAAGCUGUGGGUUUCAAAAUAAAAUUUUAUUAUAAUGAAGUAUUUUAAAUGAGCUGUCAGUUGUUAAUACUACUGUUCUUGCCCUGAGUUGAAUAUUUAUAGCAAUUUACUUUAUUGCAGAUUACGUAUUACAGGAAGCAUUUUGGGACAGCCGUAGAUGUCAUGUGCUCUAACCAUGGUUGAACAGUAUUUUUGUCAUUUCUGAGAGAGAGUGAUAAUCUUCAAAAUGAAGACUUUGGAAAAUUUUAGGUUCUCUAUAGGAACUACAAAAAUGGAAGGAAAGAACAUUUUCAAAAGGAAAUUAUUUUGAAAGUAUGUUUACAACAAACUGAUACUAUUGACAGUUUUUUUUUUUAAAUAAUAAAACACUUUAAGAAGAUUGUAUUUAUGGUAAAAGGAAACUGGACUAACAAUGAGGCCAAAGACUUUUCCUGCCACGACUUAUUCUGGAAAUAGCCGGCAGCGACUGCAAGAGAUUCGUGAGGGGUUAAAACAGCCAUCCAAGUCUUCGGUUCAGGGGCUACCCGCAGGACCAAACAGUGACACUUCCCUGGAUGCCAAAGUCCUGGGGAGCAAAGAUGCCACCAGGCAGCAGCAGCAGAUGAGAGCCACCCCAAAGUUCGGACCUUAUCAGAAAGCCUUGAGGGAAAUCAGAUAUUCCUUGUUGCCUUUUGCUAAUGAAUCGGGCACCUCUGCAGCUGCAGAAGUGAACCGGCAAAUGCUGCAGGAACUGGUGAACGCAGGAUGCGACCAGGAGAUGGCUGGCCGAGCUCUCAAGCAGACUGGCAGCAGGAGCAUCGAGGCCGCCCUGGAGUACAUCAGCAAGAUGGGCUACCUGGACCCGAGGAAUGAGCAGAUUGUGCGGGUCAUUAAGCAGACCUCCCCAGGAAAGGGGCUCAUGCCAACCCCAGUGACGCGGAGGCCCAGCUUCGAAGGAACCGGCGAUUCGUUUGCGUCCUACCACCAGCUGAGCGGUACCCCCUACGAGGGCCCAAGCUUCGGCGCUGACGGCCCCACGGCGCUGGAGGAGAUGCCGCGGCCGUACGUGGACUACCUUUUCCCCGGAGUCGGCCCCCACGGGCCCGGCCACCAGCACCAGCACCCACCCAAGGGCUACGGUGCCAGCGUAGAGGCAGCAGGGGCACACUUCCCGCUGCAGGGCGCGCACUACGGGCGGCCGCACCUGCUGGUGCCUGGGGAACCCCUGGGCUACGGAGUGCAGCGCAGCCCCUCCUUCCAGAGCAAGACGCCGCCGGAGACCGGGGGUUACGCCAGCCUGCCCACGAAGGGCCAGGGAGGACCGCCAGGCGCCGGCCUCGCUUUCCCACCCCCUGCCGCCGGGCUCUACGUGCCGCACCCACACCACAAGCAGGCCGGUCCCGCGGCCCACCAGCUGCAUGUGCUGGGCUCCCGCAGCCAGGUGUUCGCCAGCGACAGCCCCCCGCAGAGCCUGCUCACUCCCUCGCGGAACAGCCUCAACGUGGACCUGUAUGAAUUGGGCAGCACCUCCGUCCAGCAGUGGCCGGCUGCCACCCUGGCCCGCCGGGACUCCCUGCAGAAGCCGGGCCUGGAGGCGCCGCCGCGCGCGCACGUGGCCUUCCGGCCUGACUGCCCAGUGCCCAGCAGGACCAACUCCUUCAACAGCCACCAGCCGCGGCCCGGUCCGCCUGGCAAGGCCGAGCCCUCCCUGCCCGCCCCCAACACCGUGACGGCUGUCACGGCCGCGCACAUCUUGCACCCGGUGAAGAGCGUGCGUGUGCUGAGGCCGGAGCCGCAGACGGCUGUGGGGCCCUCGCACCCCGCCUGGGUGCCCGCGCCUGCCCCGGCCCCCGCCCCCGCCCCCGCCCCGGCUGCGGAGGGCUUGGACGCCAAGGAGGAGCAUGCCCUGGCGCUGGGCGGCGCAGGCGCCUUCCCGCUGGACGUGGAGUACGGAGGCCCAGACCGGAGGUGCCCGCCUCCGCCCUACCCGAAGCACCUGCUGCUGCGCAGCAAGUCGGAGCAGUACGACCUGGACAGCCUGUGCGCAGGCAUGGAGCAGAGCCUCCGUGCGGGCCCCAACGAGCCCGAGGGCGGCGACAAGAGCCGCAAAAGCGCCAAGGGGGACAAAGGCGGAAAGGAUAAAAAGCAGAUUCAGACCUCUCCCGUUCCCGUCCGCAAAAACAGCAGAGACGAAGAGAAGAGAGAGUCACGCAUCAAGAGCUACUCGCCAUACGCCUUUAAGUUCUUCAUGGAGCAGCACGUGGAGAAUGUCAUCAAAACCUACCAGCAGAAGGUUAACCGGAGGCUGCAGCUGGAGCAAGAAAUGGCCAAAGCUGGACUCUGUGAAGCUGAGCAGGAGCAGAUGCGGAAGAUCCUCUACCAGAAAGAGUCUAAUUACAACAGGUUAAAGAGGGCCAAGAUGGACAAGUCUAUGUUUGUCAAGAUCAAAACCCUGGGGAUCGGUGCCUUUGGAGAAGUGUGCCUUGCUUGUAAGGUGGACACUCACGCCCUGUACGCCAUGAAGACCCUAAGGAAAAAGGAUGUCCUGAACCGGAAUCAGGUGGCCCACGUCAAGGCCGAGAGGGACAUCCUGGCCGAGGCAGACAAUGAGUGGGUGGUCAAACUCUACUACUCCUUCCAAGACAAAGACAGCCUGUACUUUGUGAUGGACUACAUCCCUGGUGGGGACAUGAUGAGCCUGCUGAUCCGGAUGGAGGUCUUCCCUGAGCACCUGGCCCGGUUCUACAUCGCAGAGCUGACUUUGGCCAUUGAGAGUGUCCACAAGAUGGGCUUCAUCCACCGAGACAUCAAGCCUGAUAACAUUUUGAUAGAUCUGGAUGGUCACAUUAAACUCACAGAUUUCGGCCUCUGCACUGGGUUCAGGUGGACUCACAAUUCCAAAUAUUACCAGAAAGGGAGCCAUGUCAGACAGGACAGCAUGGAGCCCAGCGACCUCUGGGAUGAUGUGUCUAACUGUCGGUGUGGGGACAGGCUGAAGACCCUAGAGCAGAGGGCGCGGAAGCAGCACCAGAGGUGCCUGGCACAUUCACUGGUGGGGACUCCAAACUACAUCGCACCCGAGGUGCUCCUCCGCAAAGGUGAUCAACUGGGAGAACACGCUCCACAUUCCAGCCCAGGUGAAGCUGAGCCCUGAGGCCAGGGACCUCAUCACCAAGCUGUGCUGCUCCGCAGACCACCGCCUGGGGCGGAAUGGGGCCGAUGACCUGAAGGCCCACCCCUUCUUCAGCGCCAUUGACUUCUCCAGUGACAUCCGGAAGCAGCCAGCCCCCUACGUUCCCACCAUCAGCCACCCCAUGGACACCUCGAAUUUCGACCCCGUAGAUGAAGAAAGCCCUUGGAACGAUGCCAGCGAAGGUAGCACCAAGGCCUGGGACACACUCACCUCGCCCAAUAACAAGCAUCCUGAGCACGCAUUUUACGAAUUCACCUUCCGAAGGUUCUUUGAUGACAAUGGCUACCCCUUUCGAUGCCCAAAGCCUUCAGGAGCAGAAGCUUCACAGGCUGAGAGCUCAGAUUUAGAAAGCUCUGAUCUGGUGGAUCAGACUGAAGGCUGCCAGCCUGUGUACGUGUAGAUGGGGGCCAGGCACCCCCACCACUCGCUGCCUCCCAGGUCAGGGUCCCGGAGCCGGUGCCCUCACAGGCCAAUAGGGAAGCCGAGGGCUGUUUUGUUUUAAAUUAGUCCGUCGAUUACUUCACUUGAAAUUCUGCUCUUCACCAAGAAAACCCAAACAGGACACUUUUGAAAACAGGACUCAGCAUCGCUUUCAAUAGGCUUUUCAGGACCUUCACUGCAUUAAAACAAUAUUUUUGAAAAUUUAGUACAGUUUAGAAAGAGCACUUAUUUUGUUUAUAUCCAUUUUUUCUUACUAAAUUAUAGGGAUUAACUUUGACAAAUCAUGCUGCUGUUAUUUUCUACAUUUGUAUUUUAUCCAUAGCACUUAUUCACAUUUAGGAAAAGACAUAAAAACUGAAGAACAUUGAUGAGAAAUCUCUGUGCAAUAAUGUAAAAAAAAAAAAAGAUAACACUCUGCUCAAUGUCACGGAGACCAUUUUAUCCACACAAUGGUUUUUGUUUUUUAUUUUUUCCCAUGUUUCAAAAUUGUGAUAUAAUGAUAUAAUGUUAAAAGCUGCUUUUUUUGGCUUUUUGCAUAUCUAGUAUAAUAGGAAGUGUGAGCAAGGUGAUGAUGUGGCUGUGAUUUCCGACGUCUGGUGUGUGGAGAGUACUGCAUGAGCAGAGUUCUUCUAUUAUAAAAUUACCAUAUCUUGCCAUUCACAGCAGGUCCUGUGAAUACGUUUUUACUGAGUGUCUUUAAAUGAGGUGUUCUAGACAGUGUGCUGAUAAUGUAUUGUGCGGGUGACCUCUUCGCUAUGAUUGUAUCUCUUACUGUUUUGUUAAAGAAAUGCAGAUGUGUAACUGAGAAGUGAUUUGUGUGUGUGUCUUGGUUGUGAUUGGAUUCUUUGGGGGGGGGGAACUGAAACAUUUGUCAUAUACUGAACUUAUAUACAUCAAAAGGGAUUAAUACAGCGAUGCCAAAAAGUUUAAUCACGGACACAUGUCCGUUUCUGUAGUCCGUAUGCUCUUUCAUUCUUGGUAGAGCUGGUAUGUGGAAUGCCAUACCUCUGACCCUACUACUUACCUUUUUACUGACAGACUGCCCACACUGAAAGCUUCAGUGAAUGUUCUUAGUCCUGUUUUCUUCUGUUACUGUCAGGAAACUGAGUGAUCUAAUGGUUCUCUCACUUUUUUUUUGUUCUUUUAGUGUACUUUGAAGUAUCAAAUCUUAACUUGGUUUAAACAAUACAUAUUCCUAACCUUUGUAAAAAAGCAAAGAUUCUUCAAAAUGACAUUGAAAUAAAAAGUAAGCCAUACGUAUUUUCUUAGAAGUAUAGAUGUAUGUGCGUGUAUACACACACACACACACACACAGAGAUAAACACAAUAUUCCUUAUUUCAAAUUAGUAUGAUUCCUAUUUAAAGUGAUUUAUAUUUGAGUAAAAAGUUCAAUUCUUUUUUGCUUUUUAAAAAAUCUGAUGCUUCAUAAUUUUCAUUAUAUUAUUCCACAUAUUUUUCCUUGAAGUUCUUAGCAUAAUGUAUCCAUUACUUAGUAUAUAUCUAGGCAACAACACUUAGAAGUUUAUCAGUGUUUAAACUAAAAAAAUAAAGAUUCCUGUGUACUGGUUUACAUUUGUGUGAGUGGCAUACUCAAGUCUGCUGUGCCUGUCGUCGUGACUGUCAGUAUUCUCGCUAUUUUAUAGUCGUGCCAUGUUGUUACUCACAGCGCUCUGACAUACUUUCAUGUGGUAGGUUCUUUCUCAGGAACUCAGUUUAACUAUUAUUUAUUGAUAUAUCAUUACCUUUGAAAAGCUUCUACUGGCACAAUUUAUUAUUAAAAUUUUGAAUCCAAA